AACUUGAGAAACUUUUGCCUCGGGGUUUUGGGGCUCUGUUACCUGGUGGCUGGAGGGAGGAUACUGGGGCUCUGCUCUUGGUACCUGGACAGCUUGUUGGCUCCCAUGGUGCCCUUUCGAUCUGAAACUCAAAAAACUGUGAGUUGGGGGAGUCACUCACACUCUAGUCAGUGGGGCAAGGUGGCAAGGGGAAGAGGUGGUUUUGUGGUUGCCCCCUCUCAGCCUCCACACCCAGGGCCAGGGUGAGCGCUGAAUCUCUCCUGCGGGACGGGACCCUCAGGACCCACUUUAUCCUGGCUCCAGCCUUGCUACUAAGUUUGGGAGACCAUGGGAGCCUUCUCUCCUGGCACCAAGGGCUGGGCGCCUGGGUGGAGUUUUCUGUCCUUCUCCCUGUCCUGGACAGGUUUCCCAGGAGUUACGGAGUUGGGGAACCCCUGAGCCCUGGAGAGAGAAAGACCUGACCCCAGUGCUGGAGAACGCCAGGGCCAGAGCAUUUGCAAAGGGUCCCACUUGCAAAGGGACCUGCUCCUGUCCCUUUCUGUGUAGGGAUCUUCCUCACACCUAGACGCCCCCAGCCCCCUUCCUCUGCCUUUAGAGCCGAAAACUUCCGUUCUGGCUGUAGGCAGGUAGGUCCCUUCUUGCCAGGAAUGUGCAUAUCCUGCUGGGCCCCUACCCCAAACAUACCUCUUCCUUGGUGGGAGGGAAGCAGAGGGACUGGGAGAGGAAGGCUUGCUUUUGAUCCAGUAAUUCCCCCAAAUGUUUGCUGAGCCCCUACUCUGCCUGGGCAGGUCCCAGGCUGAGUACUGGGGUACCCAAGCAGUGAAGGCUGGGGUCUGCUGUCUGGACCUCAGAUUGUUGGGGUAGGAGAGACAGAUAUCACAUGGUGGGGGGGAGGGUGGAGGGGAGAAGAAUGGGAACAGGGUGUCUGUUUCAGAGGAGAGUUGUGAGGUGCAAGGGGAGGGAAGGGUUGUCUCCCCAGGAAGCCUUCCCUGCAUCUUAACCCUUCCUACCCCACUGCCUUGGCGGUUUCCUGUCUCUCCAGCCACAGUGCAAGCCCCCCAGUCCCAUCCUAAGCAGGCACAAUGUCUUUAUUUUUUGAAUAGCCUAAACUGUGUGAAAUAAUAAUUUCUUCCAUCCAAGAAACUCCUCACAGUUUCCCUUCUCACAGAUCUUACCACGCUCCAGCUUCCCUAGACCAAGGCAGGGCAGGUACUAUUUUUGACAGGACUCUCAGGCUCCGUUGGCUGGAAUGACCUCCUCAGAUUUGGUUCCAGAACUCUGGAACCCAGAGCAAGGAACUGAGGCCUCCCCAGGGCAGAACAUGUGUCAGAGUGGAAAAGGCUUUGGAACUUGGCAUUAGAGAUGGGACUCUGGAGAACUUAAUUAAGCUCUUCGAACCUCAAUUUUCUUACAUUGUAAAGUAGGUCAUAAUACCCACCUUAGAGAUUCUGUUUGGGAGUUAGAUGAGAGAGCAGAUGUCAAGUACCUUGCACGGUGCCGGGUGCAUGGUAGUACUGAUCAAGGGAUGGCGUUUAUUAUUAAUUUGCUAGCACUGCCAGGCCACAUGUUGGUUGAAUAUGGAAAUACUGAAGUAUUAAUCUUCAUUUUAUGGGUUGGGAAAACGAAGUCCAGAGAGAAGAGGCAACUUGUCCAAGGUUACACAGCUACAUGGUAGCACAGCUGGAACUAAAAUAUGGGGCCCUCGACUCCCAGUAUAACCAGUAGGGCUUGAGCGUGUGCUGUGGUGAAGGGAGAAAGGAAGGGAUGGGAGGAGCUGCCAUUCCUCCCUCCUUCCUCCAUAAGCUUGGCCUAGGCCGCCUGCCUUCUAGUGUGAAUACUUUCUCUUUUCCCUUUAAGUGGAGAGGGGGACUGUAGGUGCAGAAUCUGGUGUUUCCACCUGCACACAACCCUGGAGCAUUCCCCAGGCACUCCUAAGGUUCUUGUGAGACACACAUAAAUGGGAGAGAGAAUUCCCCAGAAUGCAGAGGAGGAAAAAUGACUGAUAACCCCUCUCUCCAGAAAGGGAGAUUUCUAGGGUUUGGAAACCCUAGCCUACACGUCCUUAUGGAAGAUUUUGGCAGCAAGUCUCAGACCAGUUUGGGACCUAUCACUGAAUGGAUCAUCUCAAAGAAGCAAAAGGAAACUCCCCUUGAGCCUGAAGUUAUUGGCUCCCUUCAGCGUUGCCUCCCAGGAUUCUCUGUGGAAAUACACACCUUCAGUCCACUGCCAGUUCCACCAAGCCGGGAUCACAGCGGGAACCCUCUUUCCUCUGAAUUCUGCCACUUUGGAUGCUGUGGUCUUGUGAGAUGUUGCUCCUGGGCCCUUGCAGAGCCUGGACGCAGGGCACACCUGCCUGAUCUAGAAAACAAGAGCUCCUGGCACAAAAGGUACCGCUAGAGCGACAUGAUGGUGGAAUCUGCCUCGGAGACAAUCAGGUCGGCUCCAUCUGGUCAGAAUGGCGUGGGCAGCCUCUCUGGGCAAGCCGAUGGCAGCAGCGGCGGGGCCACAGGGACAACUGCAAGUGGCACGGGCAGGGAAGUGACCACGGGUGCAGACAGCAAUGGUGAGAUGAGUCCCGCAGAGCUGCUGCACUUCCAGCAGCAACAGGCUCUCCAAGUGGCCCGGCAGUUCCUGCUGCAGCAGGCCUCAGGCCUGAGCUCCCCAGGGAACAAUGACAGCAAACAGUCUGCCUCUGCUGUGCAGGUGCCUGUGUCGGUGGCCAUGAUGUCGCCGCAGAUGCUUACCCCGCAACAGAUGCAGCAGAUCCUGUCGCCCCCGCAGCUGCAGGCCUUGCUCCAGCAGCAGCAAGCCCUCAUGCUCCAGCAGCUACAGGAGUACUACAAGAAGCAGCAGGAGCAGCUCCACCUGCAGCUCCUCACCCAGCAGCAGGCUGGGAAACCGCAGCCCAAAGAGGCACUGGGGAACAAGCAGCUGGCCUUCCAGCAGCAGCUCCUGCAAAUGCAACAGUUGCAGCAGCAGCACCUGCUCAACCUGCAGAGGCAGGGGCUGGUCAGCCUGCAGCCCAACCAAGCCUCGGGGCCCCUCCAGACCCUUCCGCAAGCCUCCCCUGUCUCUCCCACAGCAGCUGUUUGCCCAACAGACCUGCCCCAGCUGUGGAAGGGCGAGGGUGCCCCCGGGCAGCCUGCCGAGGACAGCGUCAAGCAGGAGGGGCUGGACCUCACUGGCACGGCCGCCACCGCUACCUCGUUUGCCGCUCCCCCCAAGGUCUCACCCCCCCUCUCCCACCAUACCCUGCCCAACGGACAGCCUACUGUGCUCACAUCUCGGAGAGACAGCUCUUCCCACGAGGAGACCCCCGGCUCCCACCCCCUGUACGGACACGGAGAGUGCAAGUGGCCAGGCUGUGAGACCCUGUGUGAAGACCUGGGCCAGUUUAUCAAACACCUCAACACAGAGCACGCCCUGGAUGACCGGAGUACAGCCCAGUGCCGGGUACAGAUGCAGGUGGUGCAGCAGCUGGAGAUCCAGCUCGCCAAGGAGAGCGAGCGGCUGCAGGCCAUGAUGGCCCACCUGCACAUGCGGCCCUCGGAGCCCAAGCCCUUCAGCCAGCCACUGAACCCGGUCCCCGGCUCCUCCUCAUUCUCCAAGGUGACCGUCUCUGCAGCAGACUCAUUCCCAGAUGGUCUCGUGCACCCCCCGACCUCGGCCGCAGCCCCUGUCACCCCUCUACGGCCCCCUGGCCUGGGCUCUGCCUCCCUGCAUGGUGGGGGCCCAGCCCGUCGGAGAAGCAGUGACAAGUUCUGCUCCCCCAUCUCCUCAGAGCUGGCCCAGAAUCAUGAGUUCUACAAGAACGCCGACGUCCGGCCCCCCUUCACCUACGCCUCCCUCAUCCGCCAGGCCAUCCUGGAAACCCCUGACAGGCAGCUGACCCUGAAUGAGAUCUAUAACUGGUUCACCAGGAUGUUCGCCUAUUUCCGCAGAAACACUGCCACCUGGAAGAACGCCGUGCGCCACAACCUCAGCCUGCACAAGUGCUUCGUCCGCGUGGAGAACGUCAAGGGUGCCGUGUGGACUGUGGACGAGCGGGAGUAUCAGAAGCGGAGACCGCCAAAGAUGACAGGGAGCCCCACCCUGGUGAAGAACAUGAUCUCUGGCCUCAGCUAUGGAGCACUUAAUGCCAGCUACCAGGCCGCCCUGGCCGAGAGCAGCUUCCCCCUCCUCAACAGCCCUGGCAUGCUGAACCCUGGCUCCGCCAGCAGCCUGCUGCCCCUCAGCCACGAUGACGUGGGUGCCCCCGUGGAGCCGCUGCCCAGCAACGGCAGCAGCAGCCCUCCUCGCCUCUCCCCGCCCCAGUACAGCCACCAGGUGCAGGUGAAGGAGGAGCCAGCAGAGGCAGAGGAAGACAGGCAGCCCGGGCCUCCCCUGGGCGCCCCUAACCCCAGCGCCUCGGGGCCUCCGGAAGACAGGGACCUGGAGGAGGAGCUGCCGGGAGAAGAACUGUCCUAAGGGCCUGUAGUGACCGGCAGGGCUGGGGUGAGACCCCUCCCUUCCAGAAUCCAGGCCCCAUCUCCCCCAACUCCACAGCCCCUCCCGAGCCUCAAGGCAAGUCCAGGACUCAGACCGGGGAGGCCCGGGCCAGCAGCUCCCAGUGUGACCUGACAAAAACACGUAGGGGCAGGGACGGUCCCCACCCCCAGGGACACAACCCCUGGUCUUGGACCAGUAGAGGACACGGAGGGUUCAGACCCCUCCUCAGACCCUCCCCACAUCUGAAACUGCCUCCCCCCAACCACCAGCAGCAGCAGGGCCCUCCUCCCCCACCAGCUCUCCCCACAGGGCCCCUCAGCAUCAUGGAGACCCGCAGGCGGGGCUUAGCCACCCCUCAAACCCAGGGCCCCCUGGCACCUGGCUCUGGCCGUGUUUUCUGGCCAGAGGCCCCCACUUUCCUAACUCGUGCUCCCUUCCGCCUUCUUUUCCGUACUGUGAAGAAAGAACUCUCCACCCCAGCUCCCACCCUGCCCUGGCCUGGGUGGAGGAACUGUGCCUCCAUCCCCAGAAGAAACAGCCCCCUCUGCUGCUGGGGUGGGACUGUCUGUGUGCCCUGUGGGGGUCCGUGUGAGCAGGCCCACCUGGCUCCAGACCCGCCCCCAACCUGAGACAGAACCAGGCUGAGCCAGGCCUCCACCCCCACCCCCGUUUGCUGGGGGCUCCUCCAGCCGCCCCCAUGGGAAGAGGCCUGGUACCGCCUCACCCACAGAGGUCUGUGCCAGGUGCGCUUCUGCAGGUGGAGCCAAGCUCUCCCUGAGGCCAGAGGCGGGGCCUGGGCCGGGAGCCCAGGGGAAGGCCAGGCUGGACCCCGGCUCCACACCCACAUCCAGCCUGCAGGCCUCUCUGCAGUCCUCUCACCCUCCCUCAGCUCCCCUUCCUCUGCAGUCACCCUCAGCUCCCCUUCCUUGCCCGCCUCUCCCCCCGCCGCCCCACCAGUUAAACGGAUGACCAAAGACCUUUCUUAUGCCGGAAGCAAAAACCAAAACUUUUUGUUGGCUUUUUCCUUUGUCGCCUCCCCAGCACCUGCCCUCCCAGUCUCCCACCCCGGCCCCAGGCUGGAAGCCCUCCCUCCACUUAAGUUAUUGUUUUAAACCAAAGUUUACAGUGUCUGUUGGUGGCCAAGACCUUCUCUCUCCACCCCUCCUCCAUCCACCCUGAGGACCCUGGGGCUCAGUGGAGGCAGGGCCCUGCCCCCCUCCCUUCCGCUCCUGCCCAGCCUGGGGGAAGGAGAAAGGAGGGGAGAAAGCGGGCUCUCACCCCCUCAGGAGUGGGCACGGGAGCCCUUCUCCCUGACCCUGGGCUGCUUCCUGGGGGCUCUCCAGACCCCUCUCUAGGACCAAGUCACCCGUCGUGCUGGGAGUGUGGAUUCUAGCAAAAGAGCUGGAAAAAAGUCAGACUCUCCACAGACCCCCUAUGGGGGACCCCCAACUCAAGGCCAAGGACUGGGCGUAUCGGAUGCUCAUAACACCCCUGGCCUGGCCCCUUUACUGAGAAGACUCCUUGGAUAUUUCCCAAGAACCCCCCACAUACACCCCUCACAAGCCACCCCUCCUGAGAGGCAGGGGGCCCUCCGCCCCCUCCCCAUGUAUUCCCCACCUGUGUUCCGUUUGACCAGCACAGAAAUAUUAAACGUCCUCUAUUCACCGGGCCCUGUGUGUGUCACCGAGGUGCGGGAGGGGAGGAGCAUUAAAGCUGAAAGAUCGCUCUGCUCGGGGAGCCUGGGCAGAGCAGCAGCAACGUGAGGGUCGCUGUGGUGGUGGUUUCUGUGAGUGGAUGGAAUGAGCAGCCCUGCAGGGGCGCUGGGCAUGUGCCCUCACUGUGGACAGGGCCCACCCACCUCCGGUUCCCCUGUGCCUCCUGUCCCUUCCACGCUUAAACAGGGUUCUCUGUCAUUUUCCUGUUUUCUUCCAGAGUCCCAAUCCUUUGCCCUAGUUCUUUCACUAGUUUGAAAUCCAAGUUCUUGCCAGAGUGUUGGAGCAAGGCAGCUGAUUUGCUGCAGGGAUGGAGAGGACCACCGCCGCAGGGUUCUUUUACCUGUGCCACCAGCUCUGGAGACAUCCACACCCAUUCCCAGGUGUCCUUCCAGGCCCAUUGUCCACGUCUUCAAGGGGGCUGCCUGGAUAGGCGUGUGUGUGUGUAGUGCCCAGGUGUGGUGGUGGCAUCCUGAAGCAGUAGGACCAUUAGUGUGCGUGCACACCCACGUGGCACACUGUGUGGUGACCAUGGUCAUCAUAGUGGGCUCACGGCGGAAACGGGAUCAUUCAACCUAUACAAAGGGGACCCUGGAUAGGCUGCAAGGAAAGAGGCCAAGGGCCAAGCUGCUAAGCCAAAGAUGGCCCCUGACACCUCCCCCAGCCCCAGCACACCAGCCUGCACCUCUUAUCCCGUGUUAAGUCCUGGUUCCCCACCUGCUGCCCCUCCUCAACACAGAGCCCCUCCCGCCGCCUCAGACCCCUGUGCACAUCCCCAGGGCCUCAGCCGUCUCAUUGGUCUUUAUUUUUUAUUUUUUUUAAGAUGGAGUUUCGCUCUUAUUGCCCAGACUGGAGUGCAGUGAUGCUAUCUCGGCUCACUGCAACCUUUGCCUCCCAGGUUCAAGUGAUUCUCCUGCCUCAGCCUCCCAAGUAGCUGGGAUUACAGGCGUGCACCACCACGCCGGGCUAAAUUUUUUUGUAUUUUUAGUAGAGACGGGGUUUCUCUAUGUUGGUCAGGCUGAUCUCGAACUCCCGACCUCAGGUGAUCCGCCAGCCUCAGCCUCCCAAAGUGCUGGGAUUACAGGCGUGAGCCACUGCACCCGGCUCUCACUGGUCUUACGCCACCUUCUGGACACUCCCUCCUUGAGGGCAGAAAGGAGUCCCAGGCCUGUCCCUAGGGACAAGGCCCAGGGAAGAGUGUAUUUGGGGAGCAGGGGAGGGGAGGGUGUUGAGAAAGCUGAACUGGAGUCAAUCACCCUUCCCACAAAUCACCAAACUGCUGGAACUCUCCAGCCAAAUGCUGGGAGAAGGACCUGGAGGGUGAGUCUUUGCUGACCUCUCUCUACUCUCAGGCAUGUCUUUUGUCCUUUUCGUCCAUCUAUUUCUGUCUGUCGCUCACUCGCCCCGCUUUCUCUGUCUCACCUUCAUCCACUCUGCAGGCCUGCUCCACCACAGCCCUAAUCCUCUGGACGCUUGUGUAGGGCCUGGGGUGAAUUCCCUGUCCCCCAUGGUACCUCGAGAGGGGCUGGGGAGCUCAGCUUGGUCUCAGAGUCUCCCCACCAGAUACUGUUUAAAAAAGUAGCACUGAUGUGUUUUGUAAUCUGCCCCUCCCAGCCCUCCGUGGAGGCUGCCAGGGCCUUGUACGGUAAACCUAGCUGCAUGUAAUCUGUGGACAAUGGCAUUCUCUACAAUGCAAUAAAAACAAUUACCCAUGA